AGAGAACGGCAGGGAAGCUGCAGCGAGGGCUGGCAGCUGGCAGAGCCCUGAGCACCCAGCACCCAGCCCGGCUUGCAGCCCAAAGCCUGGAGAGAGGCUGCUGCGCCAUUGACCUGUGGACUCCAGAGACUCCCGCUGUGCAUUCCUCUGAUCUGGAAGGUUUCCUGAAUUACGUGACGAGAAACCUGGGUUCGAGUCCUAACUUGUCACCAACUUCCUGAGUGACCUGGGCUGGUCCCGUCCCCUCUUGGAAUCUCUGUCUUCCAUCUCUUCAGCGAAGGGGUUGAUUUAUAAGGGUGUUUUCUGCUCUGACACUGUGAUUUGAAUUCUGUGUUUCCACAUGAUAUUCGAGAAGUCUGGCCGGAAGGAUGGAAUCUGAAAUGACAAUGGUUCUGGACUGGGCUUUGUGCUCAGCCCAGCUCAUCUUUGCCUGAGACCUAGGAGUGGCCCCAGGCUCUCCUGAUGUGCCACCACGCUUGGCAUCUGCUCCUCUCCCUGCCCCCAUAUUCCCAUGCUCUGAAGGGGAGUUCUCUUUCAUAGCAAAUCCGAGAGGAGCCGAGGAGCCAGGUCCUUUGUUCCAGACCCAGAAGCAGCCAUGGGGACCUGUGACAUUGUGACUGAAGCCAAUAUCUCAUCUGGCCCUGAGAGCAACACCACGGGCAUCACAGCCUUCUCCAUGCCCAGCUGGCAACUGGCACUGUGGGCCACAGCCUACCUGGCCCUGGUGCUGGUGGCCGUGACGGGUAAUGCCAUCGUCAUCUGGAUCAUCCUGGCCCAUCGGAGGAUGCGCACAGUCACCAACUACUUCAUCGUCAAUCUGGCGCUGGCUGACCUCUGCAUGGCUGCCUUCAAUGCCGCCUUCAACUUUGUCUAUGCCAGCCACAACAUCUGGUACUUUGGCCGUGCCUUCUGCUACUUCCAGAACCUCUUCCCCAUCACAGCCAUGUUUGUCAGCAUCUACUCCAUGACCGCCAUUGCUGCCGACAGGUACAUGGCCAUCGUCCACCCCUUCCAGCCUCGGCUUUCAGCUCCCAGCACCAAGGCGGUUAUUGCUGGCAUCUGGCUGGUGGCUCUCGCCCUGGCCUCCCCUCAGUGCUUCUACUCCACCGUCACCAUGGACCAGGGUGCCACCAAGUGCGUGGUGGCCUGGCCCGAAGACAGCGGGGGCAAGACGCUCCUCCUGUACCACCUCGUGGUGAUCGCCCUCAUCUACUUCCUGCCGCUCGCGGUGAUGUUUGUAGCCUACAGCGUCAUCGGCCUCACGCUCUGGAGGCGCGCAGUGCCCGGACAUCAGGCGCACGGUGCCAACCUGCGCCACCUGCAGGCCAUGAAGAAGUUUGUGAAGACCAUGGUGCUGGUGGUGCUGACGUUUGCCAUCUGCUGGCUGCCCUACCACCUCUACUUCAUCCUGGGCAGCUUCCAGGAGGACAUCUACUGCCACAAGUUCAUCCAGCAAGUCUACCUGGCACUCUUCUGGUUGGCCAUGAGCUCUACCAUGUACAAUCCCAUCAUCUACUGCUGUCUCAACCACAGGUUUCGCUCUGGAUUCCGGCUUGCCUUCCGCUGCUGCCCAUGGGUCACACCCACCAAGGAAGAUAAGCUCGAGCUGACUCCCACGACCUCCCUCUCCACGAGAGUCAACAGGUGUCACACUAAGGAGACUUUGUUCAUGGCUGGGGACACAGCCCCCUCCGAGGCUACCAGUGGGGAGGCGGGGCGUCCCCAGGAUGGAUCAGGGCUAUGGUUUGGGUAUGGUUUGCUUGCCCCCACCAAAACUCAUGUUGAAAUUUGAUCCCAAUGUGGCAGUGUUGGGAGGUAGGGGUUAGUGGGAGGUGUUUGGGUAUUGGGGAUGGAUCCCUUAUGAAUAGAUUAAUGCCUUCCAGUUGAAGUGAAUCAUCACUCUUGUGGGAAUGGACUAGUUCCCAAAAUAACAAGUUGUUAGAAAGAGUGUGGUGUCCUCAGUUUCCCUGUCUUGCUUCCUCUCUCACCAUGUGAUCUCUUUGCACACAACACUUCCCUUCCACUUUCCACCAUGACAAGAAGCAGCCUGAGGCCUUCACCAGAUGCAGCUGCCCAAUCUUGGAUAUUCCAGCCACCAGAAUCAUGAGCCAAAUAAACCUCUUUUCUUUAUAAAUUACCUAGUCUCAGGUAUUCCAUGAAAGCAACACAAAUGGACUGAGAUAGGUGCCUAUUGAACCCUGAAGCCUUGUGCCUGGCUGCAGAAUGAGGUGUAGCACCCUUUGAGAAGUAGCCAAUCGAGAAGACCACAUCUGAAAGUUCAGCUCAUGCCCCAUCCUUCAGUAUACCAAUACAAAGACAACAUGGGGCCAGAACUCCAGAAAGGAUGCUGACUUUAAGAGGACUCAGCCACCCAUCUCAGAGAGCACUUCAGAGGAUCCAGUAAGGGUCAGAAAAGACAGUGUAAGCUGAUAUUUAUCUAAUUUAAGAGAUGCAAGCUCAAAUGCCUUCCUGGGGCAUACAAGAAUAUGUAUAAAAGAAAAACUGCAAAUGUGAUGAUAAAAGGCAACUGACUUCCACCCUCAGUUUGAGCUAAUAGGGAAUGGUGGGGGCCAUGGCAACCUGGAGAGGACAGGCAUUCAAAGGGGACAAGAACUACUCAGCUCUGGACAAACGUUGCCACAUGAUAAUGGGAGCCCACUGUUGCUAGAUCUUCUAAAUCUUUCAAGAGAAGCUAUAAAUCCACAUUUGUAUGUG